UCUGUUUUUCCCUUUUGAGACCUUUGAUGAGUUUAACUCUUUCUAUAUUUCUUGGAUUUCAAGUUGUAAGCCCUAGUUAUAAGGACUUAAAUGAAUAUUGAUACAGGCAUUUCGAUUCUCUAGAGAUCUGCUUUCACCAAUAUGUGUGUGUGUGUGUUUGUGUGUAUUUUUGUAUGCACAUGUCAACGUGGAUGGAUAUUUGUUCCUGGAGCCUUAAUUGCAUUACUAAUGUUUAUUCUGGUAAAGAAAGGCAGUGUGGCAAAAUGACAUGUUUUCUUAGGAGCUUUUGUGCUGGCACUCCAUGCUGUUAUGAAUACUUUUUAUGACCUGGCUUAUGAAUCUAAUCAUUUAUAAUAGCAUUUCUGUGGGGAAAACAAUGGAUUGCAAAUUCCAAGCUGUUGACUUAUAAACAUAUUUUUGAAGCAUGAAGUAUUGAUAAAUUGGAGACUGUUGAAAUAGUCCAUAAGGCCUGGGCUUAGUUUGGGGCCCAUGAAAGCAGAGCCUGAAGCAAGGAGUUGGGUGCAAAUAAUUUAUUUGGGAGGUGAUCUUAGGAAGCAGCGCUGAGGGAGCGGGGAGAGAGGCAGGGAAGGAGAAAGUCAAUAAUAACAGAGUGUGUUAUAGUUAGAGCAUUUACACAGCCAUCCCUGUACCCCUCUGCUUGAGGUUGUGCACUGGGCCAUUUGUACUUCCGCCUUUCUGGGUCACUCUUGCCUUCAGGCUGAGUUGAUGCCACCCAGCUUCAAAGAAGGCUCUGGGGACAAAAGAGACACUUAUGCUGUCUUUAGUGGGAGCUGUCAGCUUGAGGCCACCCUACUCUGAACUCCCCGCCAUGGCAAUGGCUGAAAUCAGAGGUGGGUGGAGGGAAUAUGACAAGGGGACAUCAAGAGGAUCUGCUGCCAACAUCCAAAAUGGAUUGAUUAUAUACAGUUCAGCUAACCUAUUUCAUUGAAUCAAAGACUGUCAAUUGUAAGAUCCCCCAUUAAUUUAUGUACCACUAAGAAAGAAAAUGUCCCACUGAGGAAGGAAAAUAUGCUGCCAGGUAAACUAUGAUGGCUGUUAAAUGUGAGACACACCCAAUGUCAGAGAUAUUAAAAUAUGAGAAAGAGUGUGUUCCAGACUUGGUGGAACACAGUAUGUGAUGAAUACUGUGAAGCUAUGCUGUAGGUCUGUAUGUCAUAUUAUGGAAAGAUGUCAGGAAUACAUUGUUAAAUGAAAAUGGCAGGUUAUACAGUGUGUAAAAUGUGGUUCUGUUAACGUGAAUAAGCAAAUUGAUAAAUUCUAGGUGAAUUUACGCUCAACUACUAAUAUGAAUUCUCCCCAGUGUGGUGAGAUUACUCACAAUGUUUUCAUGGUGAGAUACGCCUGGUGUGACACAGUUUACAAAGGAAAAAUAAAGAAGUAGAAGUCUAGAGACAUCAUGAUAUGCAGACUCUUUUGAUAAGUCAUUAACAUCAUAAAAGCCAGAUCUAAAACCUCCUCCUGGAAAUUGUUUAAUUAAUUUCUGUUUCUGUUGACUAGGAGCAGUGUUGUUAUUACGAACAACUGAUUUCCUGUGAUGACUCAUAAUUCAGCCAUAUACUUUGUAUCCACACCUCGGAAGAGCUUGUCCUGAGGGACCUCCAUCUACCCUCUCAGUUUUAGGGUUUCCUUUGGGCCACCCAAAAUGUUUUUUAAAUACUUUGGAUAAGAGCUAAACCACCUGCCACUGGGGACUUCCAUACUCUCGGCUCCCUUGUCAUCUGAUGGCAUUUUGAUUGUCUCGAGGCCAAGUGACUUGCUGUCCAUGAUGAGUGAUGAGAAGAACCUUGGUGUGUCCCAAAAAUUGGUAUCACCUUCAAGGAGCACAAGUAGCUGCUCUUCCAAGCAAGGAAGUCGACAGGACAGCUGGGAAGUGGUGGAAGGACUGAGGGGGGAGAUGAAUUACACCCAGGAGCCACCAGUUCAGAAAGGAUUUUUGCUGAAAAAGAGGAAGUGGCCCUUAAAAGGCUGGCAUAAGAGAUUCUUCUAUCUGGACAAAGGAAUCUUGAAAUAUGCCAAGAGCCAAACCGAUAUAGAGAGAGAGAAGCUGCAUGGCUGCAUUGAUGUCGGGCUCUCAGUGAUGUCUGUAAAGAAGUCAUCAAAAUGCAUAGACCUUGACACCGAGGAGCACAUCUACCAUCUGAAGGUCAAGUCAGAAGAAGUCUUUGAUGAGUGGGUAUCGAAACUUCGCCACCACAGAAUGUAUCGUCAGAAUGAAAUUGCCAUGUUUCCACAUGAAGUUAACCACUUUUUCUCAGGGUCCACCAUCACAGACUCUUCAUCUGGGGUGUUUGACUCCAUUUCAAGUAGGAAGCGUAGCAGUAUAUCAAAGCAGAAUUUAUUUCAAACUGGAAGCAAUGUAUCAUUUUCUUGUGGUGGUGAGACACGAGUUCCAUUAUGGUUACAGUCUUCAGAGGACAUGGAAAAAUGCUCCAAAGACCUGGCGCACUGUCAUGCCUACCUGGUAGAAAUGAGCCAGCUCCUGCAAAGCAUGGACGUCCUGCAUCGGACAUACUCGGCACCAGCUAUCAACGCCAUCCAGGGUGGAUCUUUUGAAAGUCCCAAAAAGGAAAAAAGAUCGCACAGGAGGUGGCGGUCCAGAGCUAUUGGCAAAGAUGCUAAAGGAACACUGCAGGUCCCGAAACCUUUUUCUGGCCCAGUAAGACUACACUCCUCCAAUCCUAAUUUGUCAACACUAGAUUUUGGAGAAGAGAAAAAUUAUUCUGAUGGCUCUGAAACCUCAUCAGAGUUUUCUAAAAUGCAAGAAGAUCUGUGUCAUAUUGCCCAUAAAGUUUACUUCACUUUAAGGUCAGCUUUUAAUAUCAUGUCAGCGGAGAGAGAGAAACUGAAGCAGCUGAUGGAGCAGGAUGCCUCCUCCUCCCCGUCUGCUCAGGUCAUUGGUCUGAAGAACGCCCUGUCAUCCGCCCUAGCACAAAACACAGAUCUUAAAGAACGCUUACGCAGAAUCCAUGCCGAGUCUCUGCUCCUCGACUCCCCCGCUGUCGCCAAGUCGGGUGACAAUCUGGCAGAGGAAAACUCCAGAGAUGAAAACCGAGCUCUAGUUCAUCAGCUUUCUAAUGAAAGUAGACUCUCCAUCACUGACUCCCUUUCUGAGUUUUUUGAUGCUCAGGAAGUUCUGUUAUCUCCAAGCUCUUCAGAAAACGAGAUUUCUGAUGAUGACUCAUAUGUCAGUGACAUAAGUGAUAAUCUUUCCUUAGAUAAUCUCAGUAAUGAUUUAGAUAAUGAGAGACAGACCUUGGGGCCUGUCCUUGAUAGUGGUCGGGAAGCGAAGUCCCGGAGAAGAACGUGCCUGCCGGCGCCCUGCCCGAGCAGCAGUAACAUCAGCCUGUGGAACAUCCUGAGGAACAACAUCGGGAAGGACCUGUCCAAGGUGGCCAUGCCGGUGGAGCUGAACGAGCCCCUGAACACGCUGCAGAGGCUCUGCGAGGAGCUGGAGUACAGCGAGCUCCUGGACAAGGCCGCGCAGAUUCCCAGCCCCCUGGAAAGGAUGGUAUAUGUGGCAGCCUUUGCCAUAUCAGCGUAUGCAUCUAGCUACUACCGAGCUGGAAGCAAGCCAUUUAAUCCGGUUCUUGGAGAAACAUAUGAAUGUAUUCGGGAGGACAAGGGCUUCCAGUUUUUUUCAGAACAGGUCAGCCACCAUCCGCCUAUCUCUGCGUGUCAUGCUGAGUCUAGAAAUUUUGUUUUCUGGCAAGAUGUGAGAUGGAAAAACAAAUUCUGGGGCAAAUCCAUGGAAAUUGUUCCAAUUGGCACAACCCAUGUGACUCUGCCAGUUUUUGGGGAUCAUUUUGAGUGGAACAAAGUGACCUCUUGCAUCCAUAACAUCUUAAGCGGGCAGAGGUGGAUUGAGCACUAUGGAGAGAUUGUCAUCAAGAACCUGCAUGAUGAUUCCUGCUACUGCAAAGUGAAUUUUAUAAAGGCAAAAUACUGGAGCACUAAUGCCCAUGAGAUUGAAGGCACAGUGUUUGACAGGAGUGGAAAAGCGGUUCAUCGGCUGUUUGGGAAAUGGCAUGAAAGCAUCUACUGUGGCGGCGGCUCCUCUUCUGCCUGUGUAUGGAGAGCAAAUCCUAUGCCGAAAGGCUACGAGCAAUACUAUAGCUUCACACAGUUUGCGCUGGAAUUAAAUGAAAUGGAUCCAUCAUCAAAGUCUUUAUUGCCACCUACUGACACUCGAUUUAGGCCAGACCAGAGGUUUCUAGAGGAAGGGAACUUAGAAGAAGCUGAAAUACAAAAGCAGAGGAUUGAACAACUGCAGAGAGAAAGGCGGCGGGUCUUAGAAGAAAAUCAUGUGGAGCACCAGCCUCGGUUUUUCAGGAAAUCCGACGAUGACUCUUGGGUGAGCAACGGCACCUAUUUGGAACUUAGAAAAGAUCUUGGUUUUUCCAAACUGGACCAUCCUGUCUUAUGGUGAAAAAGUAAAGAAGAAAGAUAACAUUAGUGUAUUUCUCCUGUGCUUGCCUUCUGAAGUGGCACAAACCUGUGUUUAUAUAUUUAAAAGAUACUCUAGGAUGAUCACUUGUGCUUAGCUUAGCAUUGUAACUCUUUAAGUCUAUAUUUUCCUCAGUGCGUUUCUUUACAAUUUCAAAUGUUACCCUGAUUGUUUAUAUGAAUGUAGAACACCUUGACAUUUCUUUUUAUAUAUAAACUAUUUAAUAAAAAUGAAAGAUUGAAUGUUCAUGUGUGGGUUAAAAAAAGAAGCUUUAACACUAAUUUUCCAAAGGUUAGGGAAGAUUCCAAUUAAAUUUAUGCCUUAUAAAAUUAUGUUGUAGAAAAAAAAUCAACCUCUCCCAGGUGCAUUAAGAAAUAAGAAUUCCCAGGGUUACUCACCCAUGCGUAAGCUACCCAAGUUUAAUUUGGUAGCUGAAAUAUCUUUUUGCCUCAGACAGCUCUUGAAUUGCUCAUACAGAACAAUUCUGCUGGUGCUGGAGUCUGAAGAAUAUUUUCAUUUGCAUUUUAGUGGUUAGGGAGAGGAUAUAAGAUUAAUGGAAUGUAUAUUUUUAUAUAAGACGUAUACGGCACCUUCUUGAAAAGGAAGCAUUUGAACUUGUUCCUCCCUAUAGUUCUAUUGCCUUAUAUGCAAAAUUGUACCCUGUUGCUCAGAGAAAUUAUUCAUAAGAGAAAAGAAUUCCAAUUAAUUAAAUAUCACAAUAGCAUCCCAGAGAGACAGUAGGAAAUUUCUCCUUAGUGAGAGCUGAGUCCUUGAGAAGUUAAGAGACUGUUUCCUGCUUCCCACCCCACCCCGUUUUUUGUCCCUCCGUUUGAUCACCUCCCUGUUGAGUAUGGAAUGUCCCAGUUUAAUAUAAAACAUACAGUUUAUUCCACACAGCAGUUUGACUUUGUAAAAGUUUAGCAAAAUAACUGAUUGUUUUGGAUAACUCAACAUGUUUUUCUUAAAUGCUGUUUUAGUAUUUUCUACCUCUUAAUAAGCACCAUAUUUUAGAUCUUGUAUAAAAAGUUGCCAUCUGCCUUAUAGACAAAUGUAGAGAAUUGAUGUUCUUGCUUUGUGUUGUGUUCUGGUAAAGCUUUAAGUGAGUGUCUUACCCCUUUCCUAUACUUUCUUGUUAUCCAUAUCAUUCUUUUGUGAGUUUUGCAGCAGUCUUGAAUAAUACAGAUUAUAACUACUGAAAGGGGAACCUUCGUCUUUUUAAAUGUGUUAUUUCACAUUACAAUAAUAUGUGUAGUAGUUGAAUUGUGUUAUCAAAGCAUGUCCAACUUCUGUCCAGAUGACAUUAAAACCAAAGCCUAAUUGUUAAGCCUCUUAUUCUAAAGUCCAUAGCAAUGCUAUGGAAUAUCAAGUAUAAUGAUGUAGUAAAAAGAUUUCUCCAGAAAACACUUUGAGAUACUUAAAGAAAUUCAGAGCAUAUCGAAUGUUAUGAAUGAAGAGUAAAAUAAUUACAGGAAAAGAAUGCAUGAUUUUUCAUUGUCACACCAAAUAACCAGUUGGACAAUAUUGCAUUUUCAAAAUGGAGAGUUAUUUAAAGUGGAUGUGUAGCCUUCUGGAAUCUGCACGUGACUGGCAUUUUAAAACAACUCAUUAAAUAUUGGAUUCAUUUUAUCGAGAUGCCAAGAUGAACACAAUGUGAAUAUCAUUUCCAUUUCUAAGCAGUUGAAUGACACAGUCAGAUUCUUUGGUGUAUGCUUUGUUCUUUCCAUCUCAAGCAUUUAUCCAAAUUCUGCUCACAGACAUGAGGAAGCAGGCUGUAGAUUUAAGGGCACUCAAGGGGAAAACAAAUGUAGUUUCCACAGUGUGAGGAUAAAUGUAGAAUCGUGGUAAUAUUGGCUGUUAAAUUGGCCUGCUCCAGAGACUGGCUCAAAAAAGAAAGAAGCAACGAAAACAAAAUGCACAGCCUGAAUGGACGUAGCACUGUCAUGUGGCAUUUGGAAAAUCUUUAAUUAUCCUAAUGUUAUUUCACUUGCCCUUAUGCUUUAUUUUAGAGUCCCAGGGACAACUGGAUGAAACAUUACGUCUGUAGUCAUCUUAUUUGAGAUGGGGGUGGGAACGAAUUAAAAUAUGAUAGAGAACUAUAUGCAGAUUUUAAAAUCUAGUCAGUACUAGCAUCUAUAAAGGGCUUUUCUGAAAUUUAAACAGCUUGGUGAUGCAUCCUGAUAUUAUAAGCUUAAAACUAUCUUGAGGGGGAAAUGACUUCUUUUCUCCUUCUGUCCCUUUUCUCAAAAGCAUCUUUCCCCCAAAUGUAUGUCUCUAGGACAUUUUAUAGUUUUAAGAGGAAGAAAACAGAAACGUGGCAUCAUUUGGGAAGAACCAAGGUAGAAUUUAAUUUUCUGGACUUUAAAUCUCCUGGUUAAAUAAUGCUAAUCACUGUACCAUUUGAGUUACAUGUUUUAACCUCUUUUUUUUUUCUAAUUAUUCCAUCCAAAAUUUCUGGUGAAUUACACAGAAAUUUUUGGAAAUGGGACUUUGUGCAGGUAACCACCCUGCACUUCAGGUAAUGUUCCUGUCACAGCUGUCGACUACCCCACGCUGCAGGAAAUCCAUUCAGAAAUGAGCUAACAGUCUCCAGUGUAGCAGGAGAGCCAGUCACUUCCCUCCCCAGGCCCCAAAGCACCCCAAGGCUGGUAUUCCUUGAGUCAUAGGUAUUAAUAAUAAAAGCCUCAAUGCAGCUUCUCCAUGUAGUUCCUCUCCUACAAGCCAGGUGGAUUCUGGUCCUAACUAAAGAGAUGGGAGUUCACCUGAGGGCAAGAAGUACCCAGGAUGCCCAAACAGCCGCACAGGUGUCCUGUGCUUCCUGUGAGACUUCCUGGGGGAAAUAUACAAACUAAUAUAUUUUUUAAUGUUUACGUCAUUUACACUGCUGCUUUUCUCAUAUUCUGCUUUUAAUUACUUGUAGUAAAUCAUUUGUUUGGGCUUCAAGCACUGUCUUCCAUCUGCAUCUUCCAGAUUUAUCAUGAGUGAUCUUGUUCUACUGUUAAAGAUGUCAAGCCUAAAAAGUAAUAAAGUUUUUAUUUGGCUGUUGAACCUUGAUGUAGCCCCUACUACAUACACUACAAGUUAUGCCUUCUGGCUACUACAGAAUCUCCGCAGACCUUUUAGUUAUGAGUAGAAGCAAUAAGAAGGUGUCCUUAUGGUCUUAGGAAUAAUAGUUCCAAUGUAUUGGCAUAAUUUGUUUGAAUGUCUUUAUUUUGAUAUUAACACCGGCAUAAAUCUAUUUUUGCUACCAGAUGAUAGCUAUUUUCAUUUGCUCUAUUUUCCUCUGCAUUGUACUAAUCUGUUACUCAGUGUUAGUCUUCAUUUUUCUGUGUUGGAAACCUGCGUCAUGUAAAUAUCUGCAAAUCAUGACAGUCUAAAGUGCAAACCAUUUUCAGAGACUUUGGGGAAUGCAGUGAUCAGAAGUGGCUAAUUUAUUUUAUUUCUGAUUAUUUUAUCCAGAGGGUACUUUUUUAAUGGAUAUUUGUAAAUCUUCCACUUAACCACUGAAAAUUAUUUUGUUUUAAUCCCACCCUUCCAUCCAUACCUCUGCCUCCCCAAAAAGCUCCUAUUAAUUUGCUUAUCCCCCUCAUGUAGCUAGUUGAAUGUGAAUAAAUAACAUGGAAAAAAAGGC